GGGCUUUGCGAAGAUGGCGGCGCUGGGGGUGCUGGAGUCCGACCUGCCAAGUGCCGUGACACUUCUGAAAAAUCUCCAGGAGCAAGUGAUGGCUGUAACUGCACAAGUGAAAUCACUGACACAAAAAGUUCAAGCUGGUGCCUAUCCUACAGAAAAGGGUCUCAGCUUCUUGGAAGUGAAAGACCAGCUGCUGCUCAUGUACCUUAUGGAUUUGACCCACCUCAUUCUGGACAAAGCCUCAGGAGGAUCUCUUCAGGGACAUGAUGCAGUUUUGAGACUGGUGGAGAUUCGCACGGUUUUGGAAAAGCUUCGUCCCUUGGACCAAAAGCUGAAGUAUCAAAUUGACAAGCUGAUCAAGACUGCAGUGACAGGCAGCCUUAGUGAGAAUGACCCACUUCGUUUUAAGCCUCAUCCCAGCAAUAUGAUGAGCAAGUUGAGCUCUGAGGAUGAGGAGGAAGAUGAAGCAGAAGAUGACCAGUCUGAGGCUUCAGGGAAGAAAUCUGUGAAGGGAGUGUCUAAGAAAUAUGUUCCUCCACGCUUGGUUCCAGUACAUUAUGAUGAAACAGAAGCUGAGCGGGAGAAGAAGCGUCUAGAACGAGCCAAGAGACGGGCAUUGAGCAGCUCUGUCAUUCGUGAACUUAAGGAGCAGUACUCAGAUGCUCCAGAGGAAAUCCGUGAUGCUCGGCAUCCCCAUGUUACCCGCCAGAGUCAGGAGGACCAACACAGGAUUAACUAUGAGGAGAGCAUGAUGGUGCGUUUGAGCGUCAGUAAGCGAGAGAAAGGACGGCGAAAACGAGCAAAUGUCAUGAGCUCACAACUUCAUUCCCUUACACACUUCAGUGACAUCAGUGCUUUGACAGGGGGAACUGUUCAUCUUGAUGAGGAUCAGAAUCCUAUUAAGAAGCGGAAGAAGAUACCUCAGAAAGGUCGGAAGAAAAAAGGUCAGUGAACUGCUGGGACUUAGGUGAUCAGGUGCAAGGUGGGGAGUACAAAUUGAGUCUCUUUGGAUUUGCCAUUCUGGGUCUCACCAAGCCCUGUAGUAUCUCUUCCAUACUGGGCAAUAAUCUCCUUAGGUGGGCUUUUAUUUUUUGCUUUCCUGAGCUGGAAAUCAGCAUCAUUCACAAAAUGAAUCUCUGGAUUCUGCCUCUAAGGUCCCACAGCUCCUGUUCAGGCUUCCCUAAAUAGAACUGGUAAAGUGUCACUUGAAGGAACCAUUAUCCCAUUUCAAUUUUAUUCCUACUUCUCGUCUUUUGUCCUGGGAAGAUAUUCAGGGUACUGCCUAGGAGACCCCACCCCUGUGAGCCCUUCCCUCUAGAUGUCCUGUUUUCCUGUCCCUUUAGCUUUUCCAACUGUCCUUUGCCUCAUUCUUGGUUUCCCUUCCUUUCAGGUUUUCGGAGGCGGCGGUGAUUAUGGGUGUACAUAUUUGUAUAUUUUUUGUCAUCCUGAGAUACUUCUAAUUUCAUUGUAUAUAGGUGGUUUUCCCUGGAAUUCAUUAAUUGUUUGCUUUGGACAUGUGGAAAGAGCCUUACUAAUAAAAUUGAUUUUGCUUAUGAAUUAAAGCCCCUUUUUGCACAUGUAUUGUACGACUGGAGUCGUUGGGUUUGGGAUAUUUUUGGUGAGUGGUUGGUGAAAAGGGAAAUUUUUUUUGGAAGUGCAAAACAUUUGUAUUGUUUUCUUUGAUAAUAUAUUUUUCCCAAAAACUAAAAAUUGGUUACGUCACAAAAAGUAUUGAGAGACGAGGCUGGUAUAAUCAACUCUUUCAACCCAUGUUGCCACAACUUCCUGUAUGAUUUGUUAUAAUACAAUACAGAUUGAGAUAUUAACACAUGAAUUUUAGGUUUUAUUAGUGUUAUCUGGGCUGGCCACCAGGUGGCAUAAGUGGUUCAAGAAACUUGAGCUUGGCUGUAAUCAAAAGCAAGAUAGAACCUUUCCACAUCAGCAAGAUUAUUCUUAUCUCCACUUCUCUGAAUGUUUUUCAUUUCUUUCUGAAAUAGCAUGAACAUAAGGCUGAUCUUUGGUCAGUUACUGAGGGAGUUUGUAGAAAAUAGUAGAGUGAGUAAGAAGGCUAGAGUGAAGAGUCAGUAUAGUCUUGUGUUUUUCAGACUCUGACCCCCACCCCCCCGCCUUCAACUGAGGGUCAUUUUACCAGAGUCAAUAAAGGCCAACCCUUCUAUAAAGAGCUGGCAAAAAAAAAAAAAAAAAAAAAA